GCCGCUGACUUCCGGCCCGGAGGCUGAGGGAGUUUGUGGAGUCGCGAGUGCUGGUGUCCGACAUCCUUCAAAGUUGAGCCCUUUUUUUCCGCUGUGAGUCUCUACACAUGUCUGACACUCUCAUGUCCCACGGAUUACAGAAAGACAUUCCUUGCAGGAGAACAUGGCUUCCCAGUGAUGUGGGAAAGAUGGACUCUGAUCUCCAGGGUAGAAGUGGCAACCAGAGUAAGCCAGUUCGUUGAAGCAAAUGAUGGCUGCAGUGAAGAGUACCGAGGCACACCCAUCCUCAAACAAGGAUCCCACACAGGGCCAGAAAUCAGCCCUCCAGGGUAACAGCCCUGACUCCGAGGCCUCCCGUCAGCGCUUCAGGCAGUUUUGCUACCAGGAGGUAACUGGCCCACAUGAAGCUUUUAGCAAACUCUGGGAACUCUGUUGUCAGUGGCUGAGGCCGAAGACCCACUCAAAAGAGGAAAUCCUGGAGCUGCUGGUUUUGGAGCAGUUUCUGACUAUCUUGCCAGAGGAGAUCCAGACCUGGGUGAGGGAGCAGCAUCCAGAAAACGGCGAGGAAGCUGUGGCUCUGGUUGAGGAUGUACAGAGAGCUCCUGGACAACAGGUUCUAGAUUCUGAGAAGGACUUGAAAGUACUCAUGAAGGAGAUGGCCCCUUUGGGAGCAACCAGAGAAUCACUGAGAUCCCAAUGGAAACAGGAGGUUCAGCCAGAGGAACCGACUUUUAAGGGAUCACAGAGCUCACACCAAAGACCAGGGGAACAGUCAGAAGCCUGGCUUGCUCCUCAGGCUCCCAGGAACCUGCCUCAAAACACAGGUCUCCACGACCAGGAGACAGGUGCUGUGGUCUGGACAGCUGGGUCCCAGGCUAGAGUGGUGCUAUUUUAUCGGUAGCAGCAGCUCCAGUGUUGUUACAGGGACCAGCCAUGCGUGACAACAGAGCUGUAUCCCUCUGUCAGCAAGAAUGGAUGUGCCCAGGCCCUGCACAAAGGGCCCUCUACAGGGGUGCCACCCAGAGGAAGGACAGUCACGUCUCGCUGGCAACAGGUGUGCCCUGGGGCUAUGAAGAGACCAAGACGCUCCUGGCUAUUCUUAGUAGUUCUCAAUUUUAUGGAAAACUCCAGACCUGUCAGCAGAACAGCCAGAUCUACAGGGCCAUGGCGGAAGGACUCUGGGAGCAGGGUUUUCUGCGGACCCCAGAACAGUGUCGCACCAAGUUCAAAAGCCUACAGUUGAGUUACCGCAAAGUGAGGAGAGGCCGUGUGCCUGAGCCUUGUAUCUUUUAUGAGGAAAUGAAUGCUCUUUCAGGCUCCUGGGCCUCUGCACCUCCUAUGGCAAGCGAUGCUGUUCCUGGCCAAGAAGGAAGUGAUAUUGAGGCUGGAGAGCUGAAUCACCAGAAUGGGGAACCCACGGAGGUAGAAGAUGGCACUGUGGAUGGUGCAGACAGGGAUGAAAAGGACUUCAGGAAUCCUGGCCAGGAAGUCAGGAAACUAGACCUGCCAGUGCUGUUCCCAAACAGACUUGGUUUUGAGUUCAAGAACGAGAUUAAAAAAGAAAAUCUAAAAUGGGAUGAUUCAGAGGAAGUAGAAAUAAACAAGGCUUUACAGAGAAAGUCCAGAGGAGUUUAUUGGCACUCUGAGCUACAAAAAGGCUUGGAGAGUGAGCCAACAUCAAGAAGGCAAUGUAGAAAUUCUCCAGGGGAGAGUGAGGAGAAAACCCCAUCCCAGGAGAAGAUGAGUCACCAGAGUUUUUGUGCCAGGGACAAAGCCUGUACACAUAUCCUCUGUGGGAAAAACUGCUCUCAGAGUGUGCACUCUCCCCACAAGCCAGCGCUCAAACUGGAAAAAGUAUCUCAAUGUCCUGAAUGUGGGAAAACCUUUAGCCGAAGUUCUUAUCUUGUUCGGCAUCAAAGAAUCCACACAGGCGAGAAGCCUCACAAGUGCAGUGAGUGCGGGAAGGGCUUUAGUGAGCGCUCCAACCUCACUGCCCACCUACGAACUCACACAGGGGAGAGGCCCUAUCAGUGUGGGCAAUGUGGGAAAAGCUUCAACCAGAGUUCCAGCCUCAUUGUCCACCAGAGGACCCAUACCGGGGAAAAGCCUUACCAGUGCAUUGUCUGUGGAAAGAGAUUCAACAACAGUUCCCAGUUCAGUGCUCACCGGCGCAUCCACACUGGGGAGAGCCCAUACAAGUGUGCAGUGUGUGGGAAAAUCUUCAACAAUAGCUCCCACUUCAGUGCCCACCGAAAAACCCACACUGGUGAAAAGCCUUACAGGUGUUCUCACUGUGAGAGAGGCUUCACUAAGAACUCUGCCCUCACCCGUCAUCAGACAGUACACAUGAAAGCAGUACUCUCAUCACAGGAAGGAAGAGAUGCGUUAUGAGUGUGUCGGUAAACUGUCAGAUUAAGUUCCUCAGGUCAGCAUGUAUGAGCUUUCUUCUGCUGUGGAGAGAUCUAGCCAGUCCCUGACUUUGCAACAGACCUACUGACUACUGGAUCUUAAGACCCAUGUCUAGGACCAGGAGUCAGCAUAAGGACGCUGACCUCUCCUGGCUGUGCCUGUGACUCCAGAGUCCUAUCUUACUGUGACUUAAAGUUUGAUGGAGAGAAAGCUGUAGGAUCCAUAAAUUCUACCAGGAAACCAGGGUCUUCCUGUUCCUAGCACUGAGAAUGGGCACCCAGUGGUCCAAGAACACUUUCUGGGCUAACAUAGUCCUCACACAGGGCUGAGAAAGAAAGUGUCUCCUUUCCUGGAAAGCACAUGUAAAAGUUAAGGGCCUGAAUCUCUUCUAAACCAAUAAUUGACCUCUAGGCACCCACCGUAAUACUGCUACCUUCAGGGCAGAAGACACUGCUCUUUGUAACCCAGCCACCACCAAAAAGCAAACAGAAAGAAGGAAGGAUGGUUAAGCCAUUGGAUAAUACUGAAUCUGUUUCCCUAAGUGACUUAACCUUAGAGCAAGCACAACAUCCAGGUUAAUUUUUUGUAAGAUUUCUCCUUUUAUUAUUGCCCUCAUCAUAGUUCCUGAUUGUCUCUUAAAGUAAGUGGUUUAUAGACAUUACUAUUUCUGAUAAUAAUUUACAAACUACUAUAAACAAAUUUAUAAACAUUACUAAUUUCUGAUGAAAAUAAAGUUGUUUCUCCCUCCA